GCCCGGGUGACGGCUGCGGAGGUGGCGGCCGGGCUGGGAUAGCGCGAGUGUCCGCGGCCGAGCAGCAGGUAAGCGCGUCCCCGGAUGCAGCCGGGCCACCCUCCGCCCGCCGUCCUGGUGCUGGGAGGAGCAGCGGUGCGUUUGGAGGGCCGAGGCUCUGCGGACCUCUUGUUCCGAGGAAAAACCCGACGCGCCCGCUCCGCCGCCGCCGGAUGCUACCACUUCUCGCCUGCGGUCCAGGGAUCUUUCUUCGGCAAGGGCCGAGGCGGCCGCCUGGACAUCCCAAGAAAGGACAGGCCCAGCUGCUUCCCAGAUUUUUGCUGUGAGAAUUAAUUACCAGUAACAGUUCAAUAUGGGGGACAUUCUGGCUCAUGAAUCUGAAUUACUUGGACUAGUGAAAGAGUAUUUAGAUUUUGCUGAAUUUGAAGACACCUUGAAAACAUUUUCAAAAGAAUGCAAAAUAAAAGGAAAACCAUUGUGUAAAACAGUAGGCGGAUCUUUCAGAGACUCCAAAUCAUUGACAAUUCAGAAGGAUCUUGUCGCUGCAUUUGACAACGGAGACCAGAAGGUGUUCUUCGAUCUGUGGGAGGAGCACAUUUCAAGUUCCAUCCGAGAUGGGGACUCCUUUGCCCAGAAGCUGGAAUUCUAUCUCCACAUCCAUUUUGCCAUCUAUCUUUUGAAGUACUCUGUGGGGAGACCGGACAAAGAGGAGCUGGAUGAAAAGAUUUCCUACUUCAAAACCUACCUGGAGACCAAAGGGGCAGCCUUGAGCCAGACCACAGAGUUUCUUCCUUUCUAUGCCCUUCCUUUUGUUCCCAACCCUAUGGUGCACCCCUCAUUUAAAGAACUCUUCCAGGAUUCCUGGACUCCAGAGUUAAAGUUGAAGUUGAUAAAGUUUCUAGCUUUAAUAUCUAAAGCCAGCAACACGCCAAAGCUUUUAACAAUAUAUAAGGAGAAUGGACAAAGUAACAAAGAAAUCUUGCAGCAGCUCCACCAGCAGCUGGUUGAAGCUGAACGUAGGUCAGUGACAUACCUCAAACGGUACAAUAAGAUCCAGGCCGACUACCACAAUCUCAUUGGAGUCACAGCAGAGCUGGUGGAUUCUCUAGAGGCCACAGUCAGCGGCAAGAUGAUCACCCCUGAGUACCUCCAGAGCGUCUGUGUCCGCCUGUUCAGUAACCAGAUGCGGCAGAGCCUGGCGCAUAGUGUGGACUUCACGAGGCCUGGGACGGCAUCCACCAUGUUACGAGCCUCCUUGGCACCCGUGAAAUUGAAGGAUGUCCCAUUACUGCCCUCCUUGGAUUAUGAGAAACUGAAGAAGGAUUUGAUUUUGGGGAGUGACCGCUUGAAAGCCUUCUUGUUGCAGGCUCUGCGCUGGCGCUUGACCACAUCCCAUCCUGGAGAGCAGAGGGAGACCGUUCUGCAAGCCUACAUCAGCAAUGACCUCUUGGACUGUUAUAGCCACAACCAGAGGAGUGUGCUUCAGUUGCUGCACUCCACGAGCGACGUGGUGCGGCAGUACAUGGCCAGGCUCAUCAAUGCUUUUGCGUCACUGGCAGAAGGUCGCCUCUACCUUGCCCAGAACACAAAGGUGCUGCAGAUGCUGGAGGGAAGGCUGAAGGAGGAGGACAAGGAUAUCAUCACCAGGGAGAAUGUUCUUGGGGCCCUGCAGAAGUUCAGUCUCAGGCGCCCGCUGCAGACAGCGAUGAUUCAAGACGGCCUCAUCUUCUGGCUGGUUGAUGUUCUGAAGGACCCUGACUGCCUGUCUGACUACACGCUGGAGUACUCGGUGGCUUUGCUCAUGAACCUCUGCCUCCGCAGCACAGGGAAGAACAUGUGUGCCAAGGUGGCAGGCCUCGUGCUCAAAGUCCUUUCGGAUCUUCUUGGCCAUGAAAACCAUGAGAUACAGCCGUAUGUGAAUGGAGCUCUGUACAGCAUCCUUUCUGUUCCAUCCAUUCGUGAGGAAGCAAGAGCAAUGGGAAUGGAAGACAUCCUACGCUGCUUCAUCAAAGAAGGCAAUGCUGAAAUGAUCCGCCAGAUAGAAUUCAUCAUCAAGCAGCUAAAUUCCGAAGAGCUACCAGAUGGUGUUCUUGAAUCUGAUGAUGAUGAAGAUGAAGAUGAUGAAGAGGACCAUGACAUCAUGGAAGCCGAUCUGGACAAAGACGAACUGAUCCAGCCCCAGCUCGGAGAACUCUCAGGAGAGAAGCUUCUGACCACGGAGUACCUGGGGAUCAUGACCAACACGGGGAAGACAAGGCGGAAGGGGCUGGCUAAUGUGCAGUGGAGCGGGGAUGAGCCCCUGCAAAGGCCCGUCACCCCCGGCGGCCACAGAAACGGGUACCCAGUGGUGGAAGACCAACACACACCUCCCCAGACAGCCCAGCACGCCAGAAACGGCCACCCGCAGGCCCUGCCAGCCGCUCACGAGGCUGUCUACAGGGAGGGCAAGCCCAGCACCCCGGAGUCCUGCGUCUCCUCUUCAUCAGCCAUCAUCGCCAAGCCAGGAGAGUGGCUCCCAAGAGGACGCCAGGAAGAGCCUCGCCCAGCCCCCACGGGGACCCCCCGCCAGCCAAGGGAGGCGCCCCAGGACCCAGGCAAUGGAGUGACCACCAGGGAAUGUGCAUCAGCCUUCACCUGCAAGCCCCGGGCCCCCUGCACUCCAGAGAUGCUGGACUGGAACCCACCCAAGGCAAAGGCGUCAGUUCUGGCCCCUCUGUUCUCUUCGUGUGGCCCCCAGCAGGCCAGCCGCCCCGGCUCCACAGCGUCCUCCACAAGGGGCCUGCCGAGCAGCCAGUCUCACAGGAAGUAAGGAUGUCCCCGGGUGUCCCCAUCACGUUGCCGGAGGACCAGCCAGCUUCCCGCUCUCAGCUGGCAGCAGCUGCCGGUGAUGGAUGUGAAGGGACAGUUGUCCACAAGACUCUGGGAGCUGAGGGGAGGCCGGCUCUCCAGGCAGCACCAGAGCAAGGCCAUCGCAGCCCCGCCAGCCGGGUCACUUUCUCCCAGGGCAGAGCCACCAAGGAGGGCUGGGGAGAGCCUGGCAUUGCCCUCCUGGAGAGGGGAAUUUCCUGCUCACCCUUCACACACAGAGGAGAGGGGUGGCUUUUGCCCGCAGGAGAUCUUCUGGCCCCAGAAACAGCAGGUGCUGGAUUUGCAGCCCUGGCCCUCCAGGCCCCAACAGGGCGACAGUGUAGGGCCAGCCUGGAGCAGGGCUUUUCCAAGGCUGCUGAAGCCAGCCCUCCUCACUUGGGCUGACUACCAGGACCCAGAAGGAACUCAGGGUGAAGCUCAUUUUAUUCUCAAGCCUGCGUCUCAGCAGCAAAGUUGGUGUUUUCUUCCUGUGUUAAAAUCUGAGAAAGAAGGCCAGGUGCGGUGGCUCACGCCUGUAAUUCCAGGACUUUGGAAGGCUGAGGCGGGCAGAUCACGAGGUCAGGAGAUCGAGACCAUCCUGGCUAACGUGGUGAAACCCCGUCUCUACUAAAAAAAUACAAAAAAAUUAGCCGGGCGUGGUGGCGGGCGCUUGUAGUCCCAGCUACUCUGGAGGCUGAGGCAGGAGAAUGGCGUGAACCCGGGAGGCGGAGCUUGCAGUGAGCCGAGAUCGUGCCACUGCACUCUAGCCUGGGUGACAGAGCGAGACUCCGUCCCCAAAAAAAAAAUUCUGAGAAUAUGGUGUGUUCCAGCCUCUUCAAAGCUCUGCUCUUCUGCACACGUUUUUUGAAGGCCUUAAAAAGGCCACCAGUGUGACCAGGGAGCACCCUCUGCCUCCCUCCCUGCACUGGGACCAUAAACAUAAACAGCUCUACCAGCAAAGUGACCCAUCCCGCGGGGGAGGCCUGCGCACGCCCCUCACCAGGGCUGUCAUCAGAAUCCAGUCUUAGGACAGAGGAAGGAUGUUUGCCUUCAGGACCAGCAAGUCACAGGUGUCCUGGAUGUUACCCAAGCUCUAAAAUCAAAUAAAACCCAUCAGUAUUUAGUGGUGUGUGUGUGUGUGUGUGUGUGUGUGUGUGUGUGUGUGUGUGUGUGUGUGUGUGUAUGAGUGUAUGAAGGGAAAUGGAAAGCAGAGAAAAGUCGCGUGCCCUCCCCCAGGCACCUGAUCUGCCCACAGACCCUUCAAUGGGGACAUCUCUGGUCCCAAUGGUCGUAAAUAAAGGCUAAGCGCUGGAUUUUUCCAUGGCCCCCUGACUCCUCAGGAGCGCAGGCAGAGGAGGUAAACAGGAGGCCAGGUUACCCAUGAGAUGACCAGAAGCUCAUCCAGGGCCGGGACCCUGGUUCAUCUCGUGAAUUCUUGGCAGCGGCUCCAGGCUGGGCACAUUAGAUGCUGUCAUGUGACUGGCCUGGUGGCCACCUCUUGGUUCUCUGGAAAUGUGUCCACUCUGUGCUCAGGGAAGAAGGCUGCCGUCCUGACCUGUCAGCCACCAGGCCCUCUCUGAACUCCUCACUUGACCCGGAGGCAUUGGGAGCAAACACAAAGCUCGCCCCUGGUGUCAGUGGUGCAGACAGAGGAAAAGCAGAGGGUCCGCAAAAUGCAACUCCUCCGUGGUGAGACUUUGAAAAGGUGUAGAGUGGUUGCAGACAAACAGCAAAGGAGUGGAAUGGAAAAAUCUCUCUUGCUCCCCACAAGAAGUCCACUCCCCUACGGAUUCCUCAGAUGCCACUGGCUGGCACAGCCUUUCCCGCCCUUGGUGUGGGAGCAGCAGAAGUCCAGCGGGGGUGGGAGAAUCAUCGGGGUCAGGUCAGUGUCUCCCUCGUCUGAAGUCAACCACUACUUUUCCCUCAAGCCUACCAAAGAGCUAAAGUCUGAUCUGUAGAUGUCUGAUGGUUUGAGGAGAAGAAAAGAUAGUCUUUUAGAGAAGUGGGGAGUAUCCAACUUAGGGUCAAAAUACACUGAGAUUAGGCCGGGCACAGUGGCUCACACCUGUAAUCCCAGUGCUUUGGGAGGCCGAGGCGGAUGGAUCACUUGAGGCCUCCAGGAGUUCGAGACCAGCCUGGCCAACAUGGCGAAACCCCGUCUCUACUAAAAUACAAAAAAUUAGCUGGAUGUGGUGGUGGGUGCCUGUAAUCUCAGCUACUCAAGGAGGCUGAGGCACAAGAAUAGCUUGAACCGGGAGAUGGAAGAUGCAGUGAGCCAAGAUCACGCCCCUGCACUCCAGCCUGGGCGACAGAGACUCCGUCAAAAAAAAAAAAAAAAUACAUUGAGAUUACCAGGUGGGGUAUGUGUGGUUCUUCCAGGAAAGUGCUGAAAAUAUCACCCAGGCCUCUGCGCCACGCCCUGGGAGAGUACACUCCUGGGCUCACGCCUCUGCAUUCCAAGGCUGACAGCUAGAAAUAUACUUUGUAAAAUACCAACAACUUAUUCACAAAUAUUCCAACUAUCUACCAGCUCCAAUGAGCUUGCUGAGGAUGGGUAUGACCCCAGUCUAAGGGGAAAGAAUCUAAAACACAAGUAAACCUGUUUAAAGGCCAGAUCUCCAGAUGGAGAUCCAAGCAGAUGGCGCCUAAGGUUUGCCCUUGAAAACUACCAAGGAAGCCACAGAGAGGGAUCUUUGGACCUUCUGGAAAAUGGUAAGGCCCCAGGUAGAUUAUGGCUCCUCUGCCCUGGAGGCUGAGCCGCCCCUCUGGUUACCUCACAUCUUCUGGUUUCUUCUGAGUGGGACUUGAUCUCAUUUCUGCAUUCACAGCAAGGUGGAACUGUCUGGCAAGAGCUUAAAUUAGGACCUGUGGUGGGGACUUUAAUAGGCAGGUGGAGGUUUGAGAUCCAGUGAGAUGCCAGAGAUUAGUCAAUAGGUGAGGAAAGAUUUGGCCCAAAUCAAAAGAGCUAAAAAAAAAAUAAUAAAAUAAAAAUAAAAAUAAAAUAGUUGAACAAAUAAGGUUCAUGAAAAAAAAAGAAAAGAAAGAAAAGGUAAAGAAAAGAAAUCCAUGAUAAAAUAUCAAACUUUUUAAUAAAAACAAGUCUGGCCCUGUACUUGGAUGACCCCACCUGGCUUGUCUAACCCUAAUCCCAGCCCCAGUUUUAAUAAAACUGUAUUUACAAAAUAGGCAGCUGGGACGUGGACCAGAGAUACCAAUUUGAUUUUUUUUAAAUAUUACAUUAAAAUAUUACAUCAUGUGUCUUCAUUACUGAGUUUUGGGGUAGCCCUUUAAAUUUUGUAUGCAAGGUGAAUACCUCACCCCUCUCUCCUGGCCUAGAAUCUGGGGGAUCCUCCUGUCCCUCCCACAGUGCCUGAUAGCACAGCCUGGGGCUGGUGGUGUGCCUGUUUGCCUAGCUUUAUCUCUCCAGAUACUAUUUGGGGUGUGCUGUUCUAAGAAGUGAUUAGGUUAGCUUUUGCAUAUUAACAAACUACCUCUGAAACUUAGUGGCUUAAACCAACAAAUGUAUUAGCUUUAUAAUGAUUUGGAUCAGUGAUGGGGGCUGGGCACGGACAGGCGAUUCUUCUGCUGGGCUUGGCUGAACUCAACUAUGUCUUAUGGUCAGAGGGCAGUCAGGGGCUUCGCUCAUGUCUGGUAGUUGGCUGUUGGCUGAGCCCUUGGUUCUCCUCUGGCUUAGGCUUGUUCACAUGGUGGCCUCGGGGCUCCCAUGGCAGUUAGAGAAAUCAAGCCCAAGUCUCAUAUCACGUUCACUAUUCUCCCAUUGUCCAAAGCAGACCACAUGGCCAAGGCCCAAGUCUGUGUGAAAGGAUGUGGAUACAGGGACCCCGAAUGAACCAGAGGCAAUACUGCUGCAAGCUACCACAUAGAUGCUGUUCAGAGCUUUGCAGGACCAAAUCUUUUAGGGCUGUUUUUCCAUUGUGGUAUACCCUCUCCAUUUAGAUUCAAUUGAACAAAUAUAUUCUUUGGGGCUGCAGUGUGUCAGAUGUGGAGACAUGGUCCCACUGGCUUUCAAGUUGCCAUCCAUCUUCUAGGGAGAAUUUCUGGCCUUUUCGGAUGGCAUGGUCCAGGCCGGAGCACCAGCCCCAGGUUGAAACAUCAGGCAGGUUUCUAGGAAAUGGUUGCAAAAUUAGCAAAAAGUCAGGGCUACAGAGCCCUAUCCAGAGUCGUCAUCUUAAGGUGUCUACUAAAGCCUGGGGGUGGAUGGGAUCUCAGAAGGGGGACUAGAGAAAUAGGAAACUGGGGACAGAACCCGGGGGUGAGAAAGAAGACAGCAGGUGUUGUGGGAAGUCAGGGACCCCAAACGGAGGGACUGGCUGAAGCCAUGACAGAAGAACGUGGAUUGUGAUGAUUUCAUGGACAUUUAUUAGUUCCCCCAAAUUAAUACUUUUGUAAUUUCUUAUGCCUGUCUUUACUACAGUCUCUAAACAUAAGUUGUGAAUAUUUCAUGGACACUUAUCACUUCCCCAGUCAAUACCCUUGUGAUUUCCUAUGCCUGUCUUUACUUUAAUCUCUUAAUCCUGUCAGCUGAGGGGGAUGUAUGUUGCCUCAGGACCCUGUAAUAAUUGCAUUAACUGCACAAAUUGUACAGCAUGUGUGUUUGCGCAAUAUGAAAUCUGAGCACCUUGAAAAAAGAACAGGGUAACAGCAAUUGUUCAGGGAAUAAGAGAGAUAACCUUAAACUCUGACCACUGGUGAGUCGGGCGGAACAGAGCCAUAUUUCUCUUCUUUCAAAAGCAAAUGGGAGAAAUAUCGCUGAAUUCUUUUUCUCAGCAUGGAACAUCCCCUGAGAAAGAGAAUGCACACCUGGGGGUGGGUCUCUGAACUGGCCCCCCUCCCCCGGGGGCGUGGUCGUCUCUUAUGGUCGAGGCUGCAGAGAUGAAAUAAACUCCAGUCUCCCAUAGCGCUCCCAGGCUUAUUAGGAGGAGGAAAUUCCCGCCUAAUAAAUUUUGGUCAGACCGGUUGCUCUCAAACCCUGUCUCCUGAUAAGAUGUUAUCAAUGACAAUGGUGCCCAAAACUUCAUUAGCAAUUUUAAUUUUGCCUUGGUCCUGUGGUCCUGUGAUCUCGCCCUGCCUCCACUUGCCUUGUGAUAUUCUAUUACCCUGUUAAGUACUUGAUGUCUGUCACCCACACCUAUUCGCACACUCCCUCCCCUUUUGAAAAUCCCUAAUAAAAACUUGCUGGUUUUUGUGGCUUGUGGGGCAUCACGGAUCCUACCAACGUGUGAUGUCUCCCCCGGACACCCAGCUUUACAAUUUC